AGUGCAGCCCCAGGUUCCCGAGCGGCAGGUUGGGUGCGGACCAUGGCCUCUCACAAGCUGCUGGUGACCCCCCCCAAGGCCCUGCUCAAGCCCCUCUCCAUCCCCAACCAGCUCCUGCUGGGGCCUGGUCCUUCCAACCUGCCUCCUCGCAUCAUGGCAGCCGGGGGGCUGCAGAUGAUCGGGUCCAUGAGCAAGGAUAUGUACCAGAUCAUGGACGAGAUCAAGGAAGGCAUCCAGUACGUGUUCCAGACCAGGAACCCACUCACACUGGUCAUCUCUGGCUCGGGACACUGUGCCCUGGAGGCCGCCCUGGUCAAUGUGCUGGAGCCUGGGGACUCCUUCCUGGUUGGGGCCAAUGGCAUUUGGGGGCAGCGAGCCGUGGACAUCGGGGAGCGCAUAGGAGCCCGAGUGCACCCGAUGACCAAGGACCCUGGAGGCCACUACACACUGCAGGAGGUGGAGGAGGGCCUGGCCCAGCACAAGCCAGUGCUGCUGUUCUUAACCCACGGGGAGUCGUCCACCGGCGUGCUGCAGCCCCUUGAUGGCUUCGGGGAACUCUGCCACAGGUACAAGUGCCUGCUCCUGGUGGAUUCGGUGGCAUCCCUGGGCGGGACCCCCCUUUACAUGGACCGGCAAGGCAUCGACAUCCUGUACUCGGGCUCCCAGAAGGCCCUGAACGCCCCUCCAGGGACCUCGCUCAUCUCCUUCAGUGACAAGGCCAAAAAGAAGAUGUACUCCCGCAAGACGAAGCCCUUCUCCUUCUACCUGGACAUCAAGUGGCUGGCCAACUUCUGGGGCUGUGACGACCAGCCCAGGAUGUACCAUCACACAAUCCCCGUCAUCAGCCUGUACAGCCUGAGAGAGAGCCUGGCCCUCAUUGCGGAACAGGGCCUGGAGAACAGCUGGCGCCAGCACCGCGAGGCCGCGGCGUAUCUGCAUGGGCGCCUGCAGGCACUGGGGCUGCAGCUCUUCGUGAAGGACCCGGCGCUCCGGCUUCCCACAGUCACCACUGUGGCUGUACCCGCUGGCUAUGACUGGAGAGACAUCGUCAGCUACGUCAUAGACCACUUCGACAUUGAGAUCAUGGGUGGCCUUGGGCCCUCCACGGGGAAGGUGCUGCGGAUCGGCCUGCUGGGCUGCAAUGCCACCCGCGAGAAUGUGGACCGCGUGACGGAGGCCCUGAGGGCGGCCCUGCAGCACUGCCCCAAGAAGAAGCUGUGACCUGCCCACUGGCACACAGCUGGCACUGGCACACACCUGUCCCAUGCCCACCCUGAGGGAUCAGGAGCAAACAGACCCUGCAAGGUCCUCCAGGCCUGGGGACAGGAAAGCCACUGACCCAGCCCGGGAGGCAGAACCAGGCAGCCUCCCUGGCCCCAGGCAGCCCUUUUCCCUCCAGUGGCACCUCCUGGAAACAGUCCACUUGGGCGCAAAACCCAGUGCCUUCCAAAUGAGCUGCAGUCCCCAGGCCAUGAGCCUCCCGGGAAUGUUUAAUAAAGGGCCUGGCCAACUCUCCUCACUGUGUGGGGUGGUCUGUGAAAGAGUGAGAGGAGAGCAUCUCUGCUCCCUGAGCUGCCUGAUUGUGGACUUUAGGGGGACACUCCUCAUCCUGGAGCCCACAGGGUAGAUCCUCCCCUGGAGGAGGUGCUGUCACCACACUCUAGCCCCAGAUGUCACACCCCCAAACGUCCUCACGCACCACAUCCAGGUGAACCCACACGGCGCACAGGGCUGGUUGGAGACCCCUGUCAUGGACAAGGGUACCUGCGUGCUGGAGAGCGCACAGCCAGGACCUGAGCCCAUGACACGUGGAAGCCUCCAAUGGAAGGUCCCCUAUGCUCCCAUCCAGCCAGUGCCCACCCCUCAACUGCCUGACUUCUGUGACCAUAGAUCAGCCUGGCAUAUUUGAAUUUAUUUAUUUAUUUUGAAACGGAGUUUCACUCUUGUUGCCCAGGCUGGAGUGCAGUGGCACGAUCUCAGCUCACUACAACCUCCGCCUCCCGGGUUCAAGCGAUUCUCCUGCCUCAGGCUCCGGAUUAGCUGGGACUACAGGUGUGCACCACCAUGCCCGGCUAAUUUUUGUAUUUUUAGUACAGAUGGGGUUUCACUAUAUUGGCCAGGCUGGUCUCGAACUCCUGACCUCAAGUGAUCCACCUGCCUCGGCCUCCCAAAGUGCUGGGAUUACAAGCGUGAGCCACUGUGCCCAGCCAUAGUUGAAUUUCAUGGUCAGUGGAACACACAGCAGGUCCUCCACUGUGCCAGCUUCUUUCACUUACUGUUUUUGACACUCACAUGUACCGUCGUGGGCGCCGGUGUGUCUUUGUUGCUGAGUGCCGUCCCGUCAUAUGGACGUGCGUCGUGGGCGCCGGUGUGUCUUGUUGCUGAGUGCCGUCCCGUCAUAUGGACACCUCAUGAUUUGUUGGUUCAUCACCAUAGUUGAGCAUCUGGGUUAUUUCUAUUUUGGGGCUGUUAUGAAUACGGAGGUAGUGAAAUUCUUACUCAAGCCUUCGUGUGGCCAUAUAUUUUCAUUUUUCUUGGAUAAAUAACUAGGAGUGGAAUUGCAGGGUCAUACAAUAGGCUUAACCUUAUACGAGACUGCCACGAAAUUCUCCGAAGUGGCUCUUCCAUGUUUCAUUCCCGCAGCUACAGCGUCCAGGGUGCUCCACGUCCUCACCCACACUCCAUGUUGUCUUUUUUUGCUAGGGGGUGUAAAAUCCUGUCUGAUUUGGUUUUAGUUUGCAUUUCCCUGAUGCCUAUUGAUGUUGAGCAACUUCUCAUGAGCUAUCGGCCGUUUGUAGAUCUUCUGAAAAGUGUCAGUUCAAAUAUUUUGUUCAUAUUUGGAUUUUUAUCUUCUUAUUGUCAAUGUGUGAUCAUUUUAAAAUAUAUUCUAGAUACUAUCA